GGUGCCCAGCCAUUCAUAACAUGUUUAUGCAAAUAUAACUUUAGCAAAUAUUUAGCAUAUAUUUAGCAUAAUAUUGCUAAAGCUAAACUUUAGCAAAUAUUUAGCAUAACAAUCAAAAUUACAAAUCAUAACAUAUUAAAUUUGUAUAAAUGUAUGUAAUUUUUGGAACACGUAUAUCAACAACAUACCCAUAAAUAUAACUGAGAUGAGAUCUAAUGUCACCUCACUUGACAGUGCCCUCCCAUGCAGUAUCACCACAUUUGACAAUGCCCGCCCAUAUAAUCUACCAAAUAAAUCGAAUCACUUAAUACCUCUACAAGAUGAGAGAUGCAUUCUUUAGACUCCCGAAGGGAUGCAGCUGAAAAAUCCCAAAGUUAAUUUUAAGCCAAAAAGACCUGAUUUAGGAUUUUGACACUGGAGAAACCCAUCAAAGAUGUCAAGUUUGUAAACACUUGAUCAAAACAGAAUCACAGGUCACUAUUAAAAAGGGUAUUCAUUUAACCAGAGACUUCCAAAGCAAUACAGAAACUUACAUGGAUAUAAAAACCUUAACCCUUUUAAAGGUCAGAUUUGCUAAGUGAUCAAAAGGGGUACUUGAAUUGAAUCGACACAGGAAGAGUGUGUACAGGGUUACGAGUGUAGGCAAAUGGUUACUUUGGUCAUAUCUCCAUUUGCCACCUGAUUACACAUGAGAAUGGCAUCUUUACUCACCAGAAAGCCAGUAUUAUGGGAGGUGUAGGAGGCAUUCUUGGACUUGAGACAAGAACAUUGUUGUGUAGAAAUUUCAUUGACUGUGUUAAAAUUAUUCUCCAUGGGCUGGAGAACACAUAAUGUGGUGUUUAGAAUGAGACGGGCAUUGAUUGGAUGCAAGGUCUCCACACUUACUAGCUGUGUGACAUUGGACAAAGUGCUUCAUCAUUCUGAGACUCAGUUUUUAAAGGAAAAACAACUAACUACCUUGCAAGCUUGCUAGCAGGUUUAAGUGUAAUAAUGUGUGGGAAUGACUGCACCGUGACUAACACGUAGUGACAGCUUAAUUAAUGUUAACCCUUAUCAUUAUCAUAUAAGAAUGUGAAUUACAUAAGGGAGGAAUCCUGUCAGUUCGUUCUCUGCUGUGUCCCCAAGACCAUGAAUCAUGGCUGGCACGUAGUAGGCAUUUAAUAAUAUUUGUUCAACAAGUAUUUGGCAGUCUUGGAGGGCAGAAAAGGAGGUGGGGAAGAUGUUUAAAUAACAUUUUUUAAAAAGUCACAUUGUCCUACAAUACCAAUUUUUCUUGCAUAUUUAGGAAAUUGAGGGUUUUUUCCUAAAACACGCGGACAUAUGGGAAAUAGGAUGCAACAUUUGCACUAAUGUUUCCGACACAGUUAGAGGUUUCCAAGAGAUUUUGCGCUGGGGAGGCUGCUUGCUACAAGCUCCCAAAGCUCUGGGAGGACAUAGUAUUCAUUCCUCCCUCAGCAGAAGCGGUGAGGCAAGAAGCUCUGGGGAGCAUCCAGCCUUGGACUUUUAGCAUAGUGUGUCAGGUCUUCAUAGUUUGGGCCCAGGGCACAGAGAAGUCACAGCUCUCCGGCAUCCUGUGACCUUUACCCUCUUUGCCAAGGGAAAAUGUGGCCCUCCAAAGCAAGAAACUUGAGGUCAUGGGUCACCCCAGCCCUGGCAUCUGCCCAGAGCCCGAGAAGGAAGGAACAAUGAUCCUCCAGCUACCUCACAGGGCUGGCACAGGUGGCCACUGCCCUGGCAUCACCCAGCUGUGUUCGGCAGCCUGAACCCCAUCUGUGGGGAUGUGAGGAGGAAAAUACAAAAGUCAUUAGGUGAACACUGAGAAGGCAGAUGCAGCAGAAGCCUCCAGGCCAGAACUACCCAGUCUUGGACCUAUGGUGGAGAUAGAGCAUAGCUGGCGAUCAUGUGUACUUACACUCUAAGGUCACCUGGUUGCCCUAUGGCCUCAUCUGUGGCUCUGAAAAUGAAGAUUUGGAAGGAGAUCAUCACAGCUAAUGUUAACAAGCCCCUCCUGUGUGCCAAAUCAUUCACCCCUCACCACAACCAAAUGAGCUAAGGAUUCUCGUUAUAUAUAGUUUAUGGAGAGGGAAGUGCAGACAUAAAGAGGUGAAUUAUCUUACCCAGAUCACACAGCUGAUAAGUGGUGGAGGCAGAAUAGAAUCUAAACAGUGUGGCUCCGGAGCCCACAUGCAUUGAUUCGACAAGUGUUUAUUGAGCACCUGCCGCGGACAAGGCCUUGUGUGAUUAAAUAGGGUUAUAAUUAGUAAUAUAAAAAUGAGAAAUCACUAAUGCUUUUUAGACUUAACAUUUUCUUUCUUUGUAGGUUUCAGGCACAGAACUGUAUAUCCAAUAAUAGUGAAAUGGAUCCCACUAAUUAUGACCGAAAUGAUGAUACAUUUAAAUGACUUGGAUGUUUUAUAGGUAUGAUCUCGUGAAACCUUGAGAGAAACUGAAUGACGAAUGAAACUAUUGUUCCUGUUUCACACAGAAGAAAACUGAGGUUAAAAGGGGUUGGCACUCAUCAUGAGCCCCUGUUCUCAUUCUGCAAAUGGUGAAGCUCUCUAUUGUCCUGACCCCACGGUUCCUGUCCCAUGACCAGGGCCAGCUCACCAAGGAGCUGCAGCAGCACGUAAAGUCAGUGACAUGCCCAUGCGAGUACCUGAGGAAGGUUAUCAAUACUCUGGCUGACCAUCGUCAUCGUGGGACUGACUUUGGUGGAAGUCCUUGGUUACUUAUCAUUACUGUGUUUCUGAGAAGUUAUAAAUUUGCCAUCUCCCUCUGCACAAGUUACCUUUGUGUGUCUUUCCUGAAGACUAUCUUCCCGUCUCAAAAUGGACAUGAUGGAUCCACGGAUGUACAGCAGAGAGCCAGGAGGUCCAACCGCCGUAGACAGGAAGGAAUUAAAAUUGUCCUGGAAGACAUCUUUACUUUAUGGAGACAGGUGGAAACCAAAGUUCGAGCUAAAAUCUGUAAGAUGAAGGUGACAACAAAAGUCAACCGUCAUGACAAAAUCAAUGGAAAGAGGAAGACCGCCAAAGAACAUCUGAGGAAACUAAGCAUGAAAGAACGUGAGCACGGAGAAAAGGAGAGGCAGGUGUCAGAGGCAGAGGAAAACGGGAAAUUGGAUAUGAAAGAAAUACACACCUACAUGGAAAUGUUUCAACGUGCGCAAGCGUUGCGGCGGCGGGCAGAGGACUACUACAGAUGCAAAAUCACCCCUUCUGCAAGAAAGCCUCUUUGCAACCGGGUCAGAAUGGCGGCAGCGGAGCAUCGUCAUUCUUCAGGAUUGCCCUACUGGCCCUACCUCACAGCUGAAACUUUAAAAAACAGGAUGGGCCACCAGCCACCUCCUCCAACUCAACAACAUUCUAUAAUUGAUAACUCCCUGAGCCUCAAGACACCUCCCGAGUGUCUGCUCACUCCCCUUCCACCCUCAGCUCUACCCUCAGCGGAUGAUAAUCUCAAGACACCUGCGGAGUGUCUGCUCUAUCCCCUUCCACCCUCAGCGGAUGAUAAUCUCAAGACACCUCCCGAGUGUCUGCUCACUCCCCUUCCACCCUCAGCUCCACCCUCAGCGGAUGAUAAUCUCAAGACACCUCCCAAGUGUGUCUGCUCACUCCCCUUCCACCCUCAGCGGAUGAUAAUCUCAAGAAACUAAGGAAGAAUAAAUAAAUAAUAUAAAAAUAAAAUGAAUACUGCAGUCCUUA